CUCAGGCCAAAUAAAACAAGCCCAAGGGCCAGUUUUGACCCAUUUUGCCACUUCUGAUGUAGAGCUUCCAAACUGUACAUGUUUUCUUUCCCUACAAAGCAUCUUGUCAUUCAGAGAUUGGCAGAGGAAUUCUUUGUGCUUGGUUUGGCCCCAUUUUUAUCAAUGGCUUUAACACUUGGUCAUAGAGCAUCCACUGAGGAAGGAUGGGAUAUCCUGGGAAUGUUUUACCAUCUUCCUGCCUGGAGUGUCUUUCACUAACUCCGUCCUUCCCAGAGGCCCCAUGAGCGAGUCAUCUUCUGGUUUACGAAUCUGAUCCCAUUAUCAGCCCUGCCCCAUCCCUGCAGCUAGUCCCCAGGUUCCUUAGUCCGGUGUCCAAGACCCUUCAUAUACUGACCUUCCUAGCUUCACACUGUAUACUUUAGUACAUGUGUUUCCCUCCACUUGGAACGCCUUUUCUCUCUUUUUAAACCUGAUGAACACCUAUUCAACCUUCAAAGCCUUGCUCAAAGGACGCCUCGCCUAGGAUACUUUCUCUGGCUGUAUUAAUGCGUUUCUUCUAGGCCUCCCGUGUCUUGUUCUUACACCUCUUGCAGCACUUAUCACAGGGUAUUAUGAUCAGCUAUAGGCAGAAAUAUUUCUCCUUCUAGGCCAUGACCUUGACAAGGGCAAGGGUCUUGUCUUAUGAAAUUCUCACACCCUGAGUGUCCACCCCAGCUCCACCCACAUAGGAGGCCUCAGUAAGGAUUUACAGAAAUGAAUCUUUCUGCUGGAACCUGUUAGUUCACUGAUUCGGAUUCUGGUGACCAGGGUGUAGUUCAGAAUACAAAAUGCUUGAAGAGACGGCUCCAUUGUCGUUUCAGCACAUAGCAUGUGCUCAGUAAAUACUUGCAGAAUGAAUGUGUUAGUGAGUGAGUACAGAGGACCUGACAUGUCAUCACUGGUGGUCUCACGUUAAUAGUGCCCUUUGAACGUGGCUUUGGUGGAAUUAAGUUAAUCGUGGUAUAGUAUGCACCUGAAGGAAUGUGGAGCCGCAUGCUGGGUCUGCAGAAUGUUGUCACCUGAUGAAGAAGAACUGGAAGACGCUGGAAGAAGGCUUUGGAAAAAUGCCCAGAUCAUGAGAAGGUGAGAGGUGUUUCUUCCGCCUGCUCCACCAGCAGGUAAAGGAGGCUGAUCACAGGCUGGCACUCAGGGCGAGGUGGAAGAAAUGCGUGGUCUUGCCACUACAGACCCGCAGAGCUGUCCUCCAACAUGAUCCAAGAGAGCCACAAAACACAGGGGUGUGUCUUGGGAAAGGAAAAGUAACAACUUGCAAAAAGGUUGGUUCUGCUUCAGAGAAAUGUUCUAGAAAGACAGCCAAGUUACCCUGCCGUGAACUCACACACACCUGUGCUUUCUGCAUGUUAUGUUUCAUAGGAGAGGGAAGUGCCGGGAAUUAAAAUUGCGGAUGCACUGUUCCCCAGGUGUGUGGGUGAGGCACGCUUCCUGGGACCACUCCAUUUAAGCAUUGGGUCCCAGGCAUGUUCACUACUAGCAGGAGGCUCUUUAUCAAUUUCCUCCCGUGGACCAGAUGAUUGGGAUUUUUUUUUCUACCAGACUUUAUUACAGAAUAACUAUUUUUGUAUUAACUAAGCAAACAAAUGUACCGCUCCCAGCUUCUGACUGGCCCAAGGUGCUGAGCUAGACCUCUUUGCUUUGGUACAAAGAGAGCCCAAAGCCAAGAGACUUGGCAUUUCUGUUAGCUGGUAUUCCCCAGGGUGACUAAAAGGAUGAUUUCCAUUGGAUUUUUUAAAAUGCUGAAGACACUGAAAGACCUGAAUAGUAAGCCCGUAAUAAACGUUAUUCGGUAUUAUUAUUGUUGUUGUUGUAGCCUUCUGGGAAGUUGCGAAUGCCAAAUUAAGAACAAUGGACCCAUACCCAGAUGGUGGCGAUUGCAGUGAUAACAAUGGCUGAGAUUUCCUAAGCCCUAACUAUAUGCCAGGCAUAGUUGUACAUGCUUUACACACAUGAUCUCAUUUAAUCAUCACCAUAACCCUCGGAAGGAGUUAUUAUUAUCUUCCCAUUUUAUAGAUGAGGGUCAGAGAGGUGAAGUAACUCACCCAGCAUUAGUAGGUGUUGGAGGGAGCCGAGGUCUGUCUGACUCAGCACCAGGGUGGCUUUGCUGCUGUGUAAGUCAAAGAGCCUUCUCCGUUCUAAAUCCUCAAAGAAGUAUGAGUUAUAUCAAUUCAUGGCUUUACUUUGUUUAUCUUCAUAUGUGCCACAUCUUCUAAAAGGAAAACUCCAAAUAUAGUCAUGUGGCUCCUCCUAGGGAAUUAUAGGCAUUUGGCUGAAUCUGAAUACAUAUCCCCGUAUUCCAGAAAUUGGAAAUCACAUGUAUGUCUGCUUUAUGGUGAGGUCUUCAGAGCAGCCACCGUCUCUGAUCGUUCAGGGCUUGGCAUGAGGAGGUGCUCAAUAUAGUCAUGGAGAAGAACUCAUGGACUGAACUUCCUGGUGAACCAGAGGGAUGGUGCAGAGAUUUAAGAUUGCAACAGGAACCCCCAAGCCAAUGUAAGCAAAACAUCUAUUUCAUGACUAUGGGAAUGUUUUGUAAAAUCCAAGCACCAGCCUGAAGAAAGCCUGGAACUGCAAACUAGGAGCUUUGAGACACUCUAUCUUUUGAUGUCUAGUUUUCUCCUUCCUCAGCAGACCAAAUCUCACUCUGAGUACAAGAUGGGCAGAGGAUGGCUGCCCCAGAGUCCCCAAGUCACUAGCAAAACUGCCCUUCUUCCUGGGUCCCAUGCCAAAUUCCAGAGAAGGAAUUUGAUUGGCUAGCCUGGGUCAGGUGGUCAGUCCUGAUUCAAGGUGAUUGGAUCAUUUUGAACAAAUAUGGCAGCUGGAGCCCACAAGGGUAGAUCAUGGGACCGUUAAGGGCAUCAUUGUUACCAGAGUUAAUGGCUGAGGCUGCUCUCUCCUGCGUAUCCCAAGAGUCCCUGGUAGACCACAGAAUCGGCCGCCUCCUACUAUCCUGCCAUUCUCCAGAAGGGGAGGCAGGCACCCUACUGAGUCCAGAGCUCUCUCUAACAUUGCCAUGCCCAGGCCAGGAUCUAGAUGGGCAUCCAAGACCAGCCUGUGUGCCGUGAAGGAGUUCAAAGUGAGCAGGCCAUCCCUGAGAACGAGGAGCAGGGGUGUUAGGAAAGUUUGGAUUAUCUGAAGAUGGCCUGGUUCUCCGUGAACUCUGGGAGGAGAUGAUGGUGUUUGGAUCUCACCCAGGGUGGCAGAAGGAGGCCUUCUGGAGCUGACCCACCCCCGACGACCAUCAGGGUGCCCUUGAGCCGCAAAACUGCUGUCCACGUGGACCGGGGGUGACAUCGCACGUCCAUCUGCCAGGACCCCUGCGUCCAAAUUCCGAGACAUGGCGACCAACGGCAGCAAGGUGGCCGACGGGCAGAUCUCCACCGAGGUCAGCGAGGCCCCUGUGGCCAAUGACAAGCCCAAAACCUUGGUGGUCAAGGUGCAGAAGAAGGCGGCAGACCUCCCCGACCGGGACACGUGGAAGGGCCGCUUCGACUUCCUCAUGUCCUGUGUGGGCUAUGCCAUCGGCCUGGGCAACGUCUGGAGGUUCCCCUAUCUCUGCGGGAAAAAUGGUGGGGGAGCCUUCCUGAUCCCCUAUUUCCUGACACUCAUCUUUGCGGGGGUCCCACUCUUCCUGCUGGAGUGCUCCCUGGGCCAGUACACCUCCAUCGGGGGGCUAGGGGUAUGGAAGCUGGCUCCUAUGUUCAAGGGCGUGGGCCUUGCGGCUGCUGUGCUAUCAUUCUGGCUGAACAUCUACUACAUCGUCAUCAUCUCCUGGGCCAUUUACUACCUGUACAACUCCUUCACCACGACACUGCCGUGGAAACAGUGCGACAACCCCUGGAACACAGACCGCUGCUUCUCCAACUACAGCAUGGUCAACACUACCAACAUGACCAGCGCUGUGGUGGAGUUCUGGGAGCGCAACAUGCAUCAGAUGACGGACGGGCUGGAUAAGCCAGGUCAGAUCCGCUGGCCACUGGCCAUCACGCUGGCCAUCGCCUGGAUCCUUGUGUAUUUCUGUAUCUGGAAGGGUGUUGGCUGGACUGGAAAGGUGGUCUACUUUUCAGCCACAUACCCCUACAUCAUGCUGAUCAUCCUGUUCUUCCGUGGAGUGACGCUGCCCGGGGCCAAGGAGGGCAUCCUCUUCUACAUCACACCCAACUUCCGCAAGCUGUCUGACUCCGAGGUGUGGCUGGAUGCGGCAACCCAGAUCUUCUUCUCAUACGGGCUGGGCCUGGGGUCCCUGAUCGCUCUCGGGAGCUACAACUCUUUCCACAACAAUGUCUACAGGGACUCCAUCAUCGUCUGCUGCAUCAAUUCGUGCACCAGCAUGUUCGCAGGAUUCGUCAUCUUCUCCAUCGUGGGCUUCAUGGCCCAUGUCACCAAGAGGUCCAUUGCUGAUGUGGCGGCCUCAGGCCCCGGGCUGGCGUUCCUGGCAUACCCAGAGGCGGUGACCCAGCUGCCUAUCUCCCCACUCUGGGCCAUCCUCUUCUUCUCCAUGCUGUUGAUGCUGGGCAUUGACAGCCAGUUCUGCACUGUGGAGGGCUUCAUCACAGCCCUGGUGGAUGAGUACCCCAGGCUCCUCCGCAACCGCAGAGAGCUCUUCAUUGCUGCUGUCUGCAUCAUCUCCUACCUGAUCGGUCUCUCUAACAUCACUCAGGGGGGUAUUUAUGUCUUCAAACUCUUUGACUACUACUCUGCCAGUGGCAUGAGCCUGCUGUUCCUCGUGUUCUUUGAAUGUGUCUCUAUUUCCUGGUUUUACGGUGUCAACCGAUUCUAUGACAAUAUCCAAGAGAUGGUUGGAUCCAGGCCCUGCAUCUGGUGGAAACUCUGCUGGUCUUUCUUCACACCAAUCAUUGUGGCGGGCGUGUUCAUUUUCAGUGCUGUGCAGAUGACGCCACUCACCAUGGGAAACUAUGUUUUCCCCAAGUGGGGCCAGGGUGUGGGCUGGCUGAUGGCUCUGUCUUCCAUGGUCCUCAUCCCCGGGUACAUGGCCUACAUGUUCCUCACCUUAAAGGGCUCCCUGAAGCAGCGCAUCCAAGUCAUGGUCCAGCCCAGCGAAGACAUCGUUCGCCCAGAGAAUGGUCCUGAGCAGCCCCAGGCGGGCAGCUCCACCAGCAAGGAGGCCUACAUCUAGGGUGGGGGCCACUCACCGACCCGACACUCUCACCCCCCGACCUGGCUGAGUGCGACCACCACUUGAUGUCUGAGGAUACCUUCCAUCUCAACCUACCUCGAGUGGCGAGUCCAGACACCAUCACCACGCAGAGAGGGGAGGUGGGAGGACAGUUAGACCCCUGGGUGGGCCCUGCCGUGGGCAAGGAUACCCGGUGGCUUCUGGCACCUGGCGGGCUGGUGACCUUUUUAAUCCAGGCCCCAUCAGCAUCCCACGAUCGGCCUUGGUAACCGCCGCGGUAGAUCAUUUUUAUCCCGCCAGGGAGUGUGAUGCAGGAAGACCACAUGCGCUCCUGGCUUUUAAACCUGUUCCUGACUGUUCUCUUACUGCCGAAACCCUUGACUGUUAUCUCGGACUUUGCAGGAGUUCCUUUCCCUCCGAACGCUGCUCCAUGCACAGGAAAAGGGCAUUUUGUACAAUGGGGACUUCCCGGGAACGCUUGCUCUUAAGUACCAGAAGCCGGCGGAGCUCUGGCUUUCGUGUUUUUGGUUUUCUCCUUCCCAAGGCAGCUGGAUUGAAAAAACAAAACAAAACAAAAAAACCCAGGGGCGUCAGUCGAUAUUCCCAGGGCCGCUUCUCCUGCAGUCUGUGGAGCGUCCUUGUCCCCGCCGCCGGAAUGAAUGAGCAUUCUGCAGCCCGAUGUCCCUGUCCCCUCCUCGCCGGGCCAUUCUGAUUGGACCUGGCCCAGUGCAAUCUGUCCAGACAAGCCCUGCUUGCUGGAAAACUGCCACAAGCACAAUUGAUCUCUUUUUAUCGCCAUUCCAGGGGCCUCAGGUCCUACUGGGGAAACUUCCUAUACCGGAGCUCCAGUUUCUCUUAAGCUGCCCAAUUUCACAGAGUACAAAAUAGUUGUAGGGGAAAUCAAGGUGAAGGAUCUGUCCGACAGUCAAGACGGAUCCACAGUAAUCUUUCGGUCUCCUUAAACUACCACCCUCGCUGCCACCCACCCCAAGCUGCUGCCGCCUCACCUUCCUUGAAAUUUCUCAGCGGGAGUCUCCUCACUGCCACUAAAAUCCACCCAGCCCACUAACUGAGGAGCUAGUGUUAAUCCAGAGAACCCCCCGCAAUGUGCUUCCGAGAUUCAGACUGCUUCAUUGGGAAGUAUGAUUUGUUCCUUUCUGGAAUUGGGCUCCGUGGUGGCGGCGGCACUUCAAGCAAAGACAGUUUCUUGCAAGCUCCAGUAGCUCCGCGUGUCUCAUUUGCCAGGAAGAUGGGUUCCCACGUAGCAAAUCGUACAUUGUGCCCUGUAGCUCCUUAGCUAGUUAGCUCACAAGCCGUGUUUUAUGACUAAUCCUUAAUAACUAUGGUAAAUAACUGUGACUGUGGGGUUUUUAAUCUCUUGUCAUUCUCAUCCAAAAGUGACCAGCAUACCAGUUCUUGCAAUAAGAUAUUACCCUCAGAAUAUUAAGCACAUUAUUGUAGAGAAAAAAAAAUAUGUGUACACAUAUGAACGCACAACAUGCACAUUCAUCCUCACAUGUGGCACGUAAGGUCUCAUUUGAUAUUGUGUAGGAAAUCUGAAGCCUUUUCCUGAGGUCAUCUGUAAAAUAGUCUCAUUGCCAAGGCAUCCCCAGUGCCAGCUGGUGAAUCCAUGAUCAAAAUGCAUACGUAUUGUUAAAUGAUAAGGUUUAGAAUGACAGGAACCCAUCACUGUGUCUCAUGGUCCCACUUCCCCAUCUGUGUGUGAAUUCCUUUAGACUAAGGGCAGGAAGACUUCCAGCUUUCUCUUUGUUCUUCAAUGUGAAACUGAGACCAAGUCUCUCUAAGACAAAUGCAGUGUAUUUAAUGUUUGUAAGCAAUUCUAAGUGAGAUGUUUGGCAAGAAAUCCCCUAACUGAUUUCCAUCCAAACCUACCUUAUAGAGCACAAUAUUAAGUGUUGUACAAUUACUGUGAGAACUGUGAAUAUGUGUAACUUUUUUUUAGUAUUUGCCCGGGGGGAAAAAGAUAUUGUAUUAUCAUAUAUGCUUUUUUGCAAUAAGGAUUUAUUCUCAGAACACCAAGUAAAUCUAUCUCUAUAUAAAAAAUAUAUGUAAUAUAUACAUAUUCAAAGUAUAUACAGAGCCUGUUUUAAAAAAUACAGUAUUAUUUAGUAAAAUUAUCUGUUCUAUGGACCAAAUGUAAAAUAUUUAUAAAUGAAGAUGCAUUUUAAAUGUCUAUAAAUGGUGUCAUAACUAGAGCACGGGCGUUAUGUAAGUUUCUAAGAAUUUAGAGGAUAAAUAAUAAAGGUUCUAUGAUAUACAA